ACUCAGAAGACUGGACACAAUUCCGAAGGUCGCCCAGAAGGAGAGGACAAUGUCAUUUCUAACUGUGCCAUACAAACUGCCUGUGUCUUUGUCUGUUGGUUCCUGCGUGAUAAUCAAAGGGACACUGAUCGACUCUUCUAUCAACGAACCACAGCUGCAGGUGGAUUUCUACACUGAGAUGAAUGAGGACUCAGAAAUUGCCUUCCAUUUGCGAGUGCACUUAGGCCGUCGUGUGGUCAUGAACAGUCGUGAGUUUGGGAUAUGGAUGUUGGAGGAGAAUUUACACUAUGUGCCCUUUGAGGAUGGCAAACCAUUUGACUUGCGCAUCUACGUGUGUCACAAUGAGUAUGAGGUAAAGGUAAAUGGUGAAUACAUUUAUGCCUUUGUCCAUCGAAUCCCGCCAUCAUAUGUGAAGAUGAUUCAAGUGUGGAGAGAUGUCUCCCUGGACUCAGUGCUUGUCAACAAUGGACGGAGAUGAUCACACUCCUCAUUGUUGAGGAAACCCUCUUUCUACCUGACCAUGGGAUUCCUAGAGCCUGCUAACAGAAUAAUCCCUCCUCAACCCCUUCCCCUACACUUGGUCAUUAAAACAGCACCAAACCGUA